GUGUCGCGGGUCGGAGCUCGGUCCUGCUGGAGGCCACGGGUGCCACACACUCGGUCCCGACAUGAUGGCGAGCAUGCGAGUGGUGAAGGAGCUGGAGGAUCUUCAGAAGAAGCCUCCCCCAUACCUGCGGAACCUGUCCAGCGAUGAUGCCAAUGUCCUGGUGUGGCACGCUCUCCUCCUACCCGACCAACCUCCCUACCACCUGAAAGCCUUCAACCUGCGCAUCAGCUUCCCGCCGGAGUAUCCGUUCAAGCCUCCCAUGAUCAAAUUCACAACCAAGAUCUACCACCCCAACGUGGACGAGAACGGACAGAUUUGCCUGCCCAUCAUCAGCAGUGAGAACUGGAAGCCUUGCACCAAGACUUGCCAAGUCCUGGAGGCCCUCAAUGUGCUGGUGAAUAGACCGAAUAUCAGGGAGCCCCUGCGGAUGGACCUCGCUGACCUGCUGACACAGAAUCCGGAGCUGUUCAGAAAGAAUGCCGAAGAGUUCACCCUCCGAUUCGGAGUGGACCGGCCCUCCUAACUCAUGUUCUGACCCUCUGUGCACUGGAUCCUCGGCAUAGCGGACGGACACACCUCAUGGACUGAGGCCAGAGCCCCCUGUGGCCCAUUCCCCAUUCAUUUUUCCCUUCUUAGGUUGUUAGUCAUUAGUUUGUGUGUGUGUGUGGUGGAGGGAAGGGAGCUAUGAGUGUGUGUGUUGUGUAUGGACUCACUCCCAGGUUCACCUGGCCACAGGUGCACCCUUCCCACACCCUUUACAUUCCCCAGAGCCAAGGGAGUUUAAGUUUGCAGUUACAGGCCAGUUCUCCAGCUCUCCAUCUUAGAGAGACAGGUCACCUUGCAGGCCUGCUUGCAGGAAAUGAAUCCAGCAGCCAACUCGAAUCCCCCUAGGGCUCAGGCACUGAGGGCCUGGGGACAGUGGAGCAUAUGGGUGGGAGACAGAUGGAGGGUACCCUAUUUACAACUGAGUCAGCCAAGCCACUGAUGGGAAUAUACAGAUUUAGGUGCUAAACCAUUUAUUUUCCACGGAUGAGUCACAAUCUGAAGAAUCAAACUUCCAUCCUGAAAAUCUAUAUGUUUCAAAACCACUUGCCAUCCUGUUAGAUUGCCAGUUCCUGGGACCAGGCCUCAGACUGUGAAGUAUAUAUCCUCCAGCAUUCAGUCCAGGGGGAGCCACGGAAACCAUGUUCUUGCUUAAGCCAUUAAAGUCAGAGAUGAA